AUUGUUUGCUUGUUUUGUUCCGGAGUCGGGGCCGGGAGGGAGUGCAGGAGGAGGGAUCCAAGCUUCCAAGCCUCUGCUCCGCUCUCCUUCUAUCCAGUUGGUCUUUAGGGCACUGAAGGAAACUCUUCUUCAGAAAUAACCUUUUAACUUUUCUUCUGUCAGCUGCCUGCCAAUCACGGAGCCAGAGGCUGAGGGGAGGCUUUGAGCCGGUCUGCGAGUCCGGAAGGCAAAGAUCGCGAAGCUUGGCGCUCCAGAACGCUCAGGGGGCAGGUAGCGCUGGUGGAUUGGAAUCUUGAAGCAGGUGUACAGUGUAAAGCUGCCCUGGAUGAGCAGUUUGAACCUCAGAAGACUCUGUUCAUCCAGUGCGAUGUGGCUGACCAGCAACAACUGAGAGACACUUUUAGAAAAGUUGUAGACCACUUUGGAAGACUGGACAUUUUGGUCAAUAAUGCUGGAGUGAAUAAUGAGAAAAACUGGGAAAAAACUCUGCAAAUUAAUUUGGUUUCUGUUAUCAGUGGAACCUAUCUUGGUUUGGAUUACAUGAGUAAGCAAAAUGGAGGUGAAGGCGGCAUCAUUAUCAAUAUGUCAUCUUUAGCAGGACUCAUGCCCGUUGCACAGCAGCCGGUUUAUUGUGCUUCAAAGCAUGGCAUAGUUGGAUUCACACGCUCAGCAGCGUUGGCUGCUAAUCUUAUGAACAGUGGUGUGAGACUGAAUGCCAUUUGUCCAGGCUUUGUUAACACAGCCAUCCUUGAAUCAAUUGAAAAAGAAGAAAACAUGGGACAAUAUAUAGAAUAUAAGGAUCAUAUCAAGGAUAUGAUUAAAUACUAUGGAAUUUUGGACCCACCAUUGAUUGCCAAUGGAUUGAUAACACUCAUUGAAGAUGAUGCUUUAAAUGGUGCUAUUAUGAAGAUCACAACUUCUAAGGGAAUUCAUUUUCAAGACUAUGAUACAACUCCAUUUCAAGCAAAAACCCAAUGAACAGCUUAUGUGUUAGCCAUAGCUGAAAAUAAGCACAAAUAGCUUAUAUUCAGAUCCUAUCUUCAUUUGAAUAUAGCUUUUAAAUGAAAUGUUACAGUUUGAAGUUUUCCUUCAUGCACUUGGUGAUAAACGUUUUCUAAAUUUUUAGUUAAGUAUAUGGAUAAAAAGUUAUGAACUAUUAAAAAUGUGAUGUGGACCAAAGGCUAGGUUGUAAUCUUGAUAGUCUAAAAAAUGAUCAAAACAAAUGAUUUUCAAGGAAUAUUCAAUAUUCUGCCUUUCAGAAAGUGUAUUUAUAUCUGUGCUUCAUAAAUAUUAAUGUUCUUCAGAACAUCAUUUUAAAGGAGAUACUUGAAUUGUUAUUUAAAUCAAACCAGAUGUAAAACACUCACAUACAAGUUCAUACUUUAAAAGAGGAAAGCUACUUAACAAUGACAAAUAUUUCACAAUAAUAAUUUUUACUUAUAUACCAUCUUUCAACUGAACAUUUCAGUUCUUCCAAGAGCUUCUUAGAGUAGUAUAUUUUGGGGGCAGUCAAGGAAUAAACUACAGUGUAAACAUAUCCCAGAUGAAAACUGCUGUAUGGAAAAAUGACAGAAAGUAACUGAUUGACACUGUUGAUUCACAGUUCAGCCUCCUAUCUGGGAAAGACAUUUCUUUCCUCUGCUCACUUUAAGAACUUUUACCGACUCCAAAAAUCUCAGGAAUUAAACUUUUAACAGUUACAGCAAUAAAGAAUAGUUAGUACUCCAAAAAUAUUAUAUUUAAGAUGCUCAACAAGAAAAAAAUGCAAAUGUAAUAUUUUUUUCAAAUUACUUCUUUAUUGACUUGUCCAAAUUUCAAAAGUGCCUACCCUUCAAUAAAACUUUUUUAUUCUGAUCUCCAUAAAUUACUUAGUCUUCUAUGUAUAGCUAUCAAGGAAAUAAAACCAAUUUUGCCACAGCCACAACUGUAAAUGUUUUUGUACCCAUGCUGAAACUCAUAACAACACAGACAUAAAAAUAGCUGUGAGGUUUUGCUUUUUUUGUUGUCAGCUAUCUUAAGAAUCAUUAAAUACACCUGCUUUGGGUAAAACUCUUUGCAAGCAGUAAUUAACACUAGUAACAGUGAAAGCACAAGAUUUCCAAAUCAGUCGUUUUCUCAAAAAAAUAUCGUAUAAGUGACUCAUCCUGUCUGCUAACUCCAGACCUCCCAGCUUGAAGCCAAAUCUUUCCAUGUGAGAUUGAUAUGGAUUUCCUAGAAGUACUGGAAUGUUGUCAUAUCUUGCCCUAUUUUAAUUCUGCUAUAGAAAACAAUUGCCUUCACUUUUAAGGAGUAAUUUGAAUAUUAAUAACUCUGGUCUAGAUUUUCAUAUAAUGUAUUAAAGACAAAGUAGUGAACAUCAAUGAACAUCUGAUAGAGAUAAACUGUAAUCAGGCAUAAGCUUGUUUGUAUGUUCUGGCAGUGACUAAUCAGUAAAUGAUGUCGGUUUGCCCAGUAUCACUUAUCUUCUGUAUUUUUCCUCUGUCGUGUAAAUAGUAUAACCUUUUCAUUUAUGGACAAUUUUUUGGACUAGUAGCCUUCAAUAUACAUUCUGCUUUGAAUUAAUUUUUUCAAAUCAAUAAAUUAUGUAGACAUUUAAAAUCAAAUAUCAAGUAGAAUUGAAAAAUGUGAGUUACAUAAGUUAAAAACUUACUUUAAAUCUUACCUUCUAUAGGUAGCUCUAAAUAAAUUCAUAUGGUUAUAUGGCAUCUCUGGUGUAUACUGAUUGAGAAAAUAAUUAAACUGAAGUUAGGGGAGGGG